GCAUCCCCCCUAACACACACAAACCCUGCAGCCCCAUCACCUCUCUGGGGUCCAGGGACUCAGUUACAGCUCCCAACACCUUCUAAAUAGACAACUGCCCCACAUACACACUCACAGCUCUAACACCUCUAAAACACAACUGCUCCACCUACAACACCCAGCCCACACACUUCCACACACACACUCUACAUACAGAUACCCCCCGACAUCCAGCUACCUCACAUGCACAUACCCCCAAACACACAACCACCACAUGCUUACCCACAACCUGCAACACCUCCCUGACACCAGGAACCUGGUUACAGCCCUCAUACCUGUGCAUGCACGGACGAUAGCCUGUGGCACAUCUCUGAUAUCAGAGACCCAUUCUUCCCUUCCCACGUAUGGAGGGACCUCAGGUCUCUAACGCCUCCCCAGACCCUUGCAGGUACCCAAUUAAAAUCCCAAUAACCUUUCCAGAGACACUCCCCAGCUCCUCCCCAAAACCACAGUGCAUCCUCCACCAACCACAACACCUUUCCAGGCACAUGUUCACAGCCCUAGUACUUAACCAAAACCCACAUUUUUAUGACCCCCCAAUACAUCCCUAAACACCCCAACACACACACAAUCACACACACACACACACACAGCUAUCACACCCUCAGCAUAUCAACCCCCUAUCCAACCCCAACACUGCCAGAUACACCCAGGACCCAGCUACAGCCCUGCUACCUUCCCACUGACUCAUACCCUCAAAGCCCUGACACCUCCCCAGACACACACACUCUGCCCACAGCCCCCAACGUUUCUCCCAGCUAUAGCUCAGCACUUCCCCAAACACCGGUAUCAUCCCCUAUACCUUUCCAAACAUACAGCCUCCCCCUACAACACACAUACACUCACUGCUUCAAACACCCACUCAAACAAGAACACCCUCUGUAGCCACAACAUUUGCCUCAAACACACAGACAUGGCUUCGGUUCUAGUAUAUCUCUAACAGAUCAGGCCCCGAAGCUUCUAAUACCUCCUGAAACUUGUGCACACUGCCUCCUGGAUCCCGGCACCUCCUCGACAGGCAGUCCUAAUGGCCCGGCCCCACCGCUUCCCAGACAGUCUCAGCUCCGGUACUUUUCCUCAGCCACCUAAGGGCCCAGGGACACCCCUACACCUCUCCAAACACCCCGAUACCACACCUGUACACAAAGACAGCCUCAGCUAGUCACAACCCUGCACCCAUUCUGUGCUCCGCCUGCACCCCACGGCACCCUGUCACAUACCCCGCCUAAUCCUUCUGCAGCCCUCACUCCCACCGUUGGCACAUUCCAGCACACCCUCUCCCCCACCUUGUUCCCCUAGACAGCCUCAGCCUGUCACACACAUUGCUCACUCUUGUGUGCUCUCGCUCUCUCUCUCUCUGCUGCCCAGGCCUCCCGCUCUUCCCAGAGCCUCCUCUGCCUGGGGAGGCAUCUCCACCCCUUCACCGCCCCAGGCCUUUCAUUCCUGGACAGUGAGGCUGGACAUCUGGUUCAAAGCUGCCCCACCCAAGACCCUGUGCUCUGGGCACCCUGGCCUGGGCUUAAAGGUUUGGGGCCUCUUUGGGGUGGGGGCAGAGCCCCUUGGCACCUGGUCAUCCUGGUCUUUCAGCCAGGAACUCUCAGUACCCAGCCCUGCCCUGGCUCUGGCAUGUAUGUGGGAGAGAGGGACAGGGGGAGUUGCCCCCAGCCCACACUUUUUCAAGUGCUUGCCAAAUCACUGCCUCCCUCCCCCAACCCCUUGGCUCACCUGAGAGGGACAUGGGGCCUGGGGCUUCAGGGAGAGGGAUGGGGAAGGUGCUGGAUUGACAUACUACCCCCCACCCCCAAAUCCAGGCUGCGGGGCUUGGUCUCCCUGGGAGUCAGUUCCGACAGUGAAGGUUACUUUACUAGAUGCAUGAUUUUAAACGGAAUCUCCACCAUCUGUUCCACCCCCUAAUUACAGAUGCACAGAAUCCGCCUCAGAGGGCAGCAUGAGGGGAGUGAUUUAGAGGCUGAGCUGCUUCUGCCUGCAUUAGGACUGGGGAGAUAGGGGGGCUCUGGGUAUUGCUCACAGCCCCCAAAUCCCUUCUCUUUCCUAGAGGUCCCUCGUGCCUCCUCUCUUGCUGAGGGAAGGCUCACAGAAGGGCUCCACUGAUCCCCAAGACCCUAAAGAAGAAGCAACUGCAGUGCUGUGGGAAGGGUCCCCAAGACAUCGCCUGUGUCCCAGCCCAGCAAGUCCUGGGAUGCAGGCUCCAUUAGGGCCUUAAAAAAUUCAGUGAAUCGAUCUCCUGCCUGCCUCUUGUGCCCUGGGGAGCCGCAGGCACUGGCUUAGCCCAGCUGUCUGCCCACCCUGGGGGGAUAGCAGGGAUUGGUGAGAUAGGGAGGGGUUCAGAGCAGAGGUGGGGCAGCCAGGUUCUGGCAGCAAAGCCCAUGGGCAGGCAUGCCAAGACCCACCGGGGGUGUUUGCACAUAUGUGCCCAUCCGCCCUGGCACAGCUGGCAUGCCUGACCCCAGCUGGAGCCGUGGCUGUGGGACUGGGGCAGCACCAAGGGCCAGAGGGAAUGGGCCAGGGCCUGGGUCUUAGGGUUCUGAGGGACACACGGCUACGCCCUGAGAAUGGGUCCAUCUUUGCCCAUGGACACCAGGGACCUGGGUCCCAGCCUGCCUGGGGGUAGUGGUGGCGGCAGCAGUGGGCACACUGCGGUAGACUCUGGGGCAUUCACUGCAGGGAGAGAGGGAGAGAGGUUGGGCUGGAGGAAUUUUAAAGAUUGCUGCAGGCAGGAGGGUCUCUGGAACCCUGUGGAGCGGGCAGUCAUGCAGAAGUAAUCCUAUCGCUGCCUGCCUGGAGGAGUGGAGGGGGAGGGGAGGGACGGAGCUGCUCCCCCUUCCCCACCUCAGCCCCUGCCCCAGCCAGCCCUGGAGGGAGCCCGGGACCCUAGGGGCCUUCCCUGAGGAGACACCGUGUCUACUCCGUUCCACCGAGGCCUGUGUCCCCUGGAGGGGCAGCACCGCAGCUGUUGCUCAGCUCCUUGCUCUGGGUUUUAUAAAUAAUGCAGCUCGGAGGUGGGGCCAACUCUGCCCCUGGUCACCUUGGGUCACCCAGUAUGGAACCUCCAGCUGGCAGGCCUUUGGCAGAGCCCCUCUCCCGUCCAGCCUGCGCCUCCUCGUCUGCUGUGUGAGCUUGGGCCAGGGGCCCAAGCCUCUCUGAGCUGGGCCCGAGGUAGAGGAGUGCGGAAGAACCCAGAAACCCUGGGUCCUUUCGUCCCACCCCCAGCCCUCACAGGUUAACCGGCAGCCGGCUCAGCCAAUCCAGGCUAGAGAGGGAUGACCUGUCUACAGGGGCCUCCUGCGUUCCGGCCCCUCCAUUUUGCAGAUGGAGCAACCGAGUCCAGAGGGGUGCAAGGGUGGUCAAGGCCAGCCAGCUGGGGAGCCCCCUCCUUCCUGCCCCAUUCUGCUGUCACUCAGGCUCUUCUCAGCCUCAGCUCAGCUAAGAGCAGGGCCUGGGGGGGGGAGGGCGGGGGAUGUUUGGGAAAGUGGUUGCGGCUGAGAGGUUGCCAUGGCGAUGCUGCAGGAUGCCGAGCUGAAGUGGGGGUCCCACAGGGUCUCUGGGGCCCCCAGCUCCGCACCCCUGUGGUCUUCUCCUCCCCAUCUCCUGUCCCCCACCCAGAUGUCUGUCAGGCGGCUCCGGUGACAGGCUGGGUGGGUGACAGGUGGUGCAGGUGAUGGGCUGGGUGGGUGACGAGCUGGGUGGGUGACAGGUGGUGCGGGUGCGAGGCAGGCAGGUGACAAGCUGGGUGGUGACGGGCUCUGUGGAUGACAGGCAGGGGGUGUGGUUGGCGAGGAUGCUGUCUCCUGGCUGGUGGCCUGUUGCAGCCCCCUACCCUCAUGCGUGUGCACACACAUAGACUCUGGGCUCAGAGCUUGGGGCUAAGAUACUAAUGAGGCUUAUUACUUGUGGAGGGGCAGGUGCCUAGGCUCACUAAUGAGAGGCCUUUAACAAAUAGGGGAGACAGCUAGGGGGCUUCGAGGAAUUCGGCUGGCCCUUCUGGGCUGAGACCCUGGGGGUCCUGACCUGGCUCAAGGAUGAAGCUGGAUCGCCUCCAGCCAGGUCGGGGAUCCCUCUUCCCCCUUCUCCCUGGCCACUGGAUUUAUGUUAAUACUAACCACAAUUAUGAUCGCUACCAUUGUUCAAGCACUUAUUAUGUGUCAGGCACUGUGCCAAGGCCUUUGCAUGCAUUUUCUCAUUUCAACUCAACAGUCCUAGGAGAGAGGCACUAUUACCCCAUUUUACAGAUGGGGAAUCUGAGGCUGAGAAAAGGCACAGGACUUCAUAUAACAAGUUACUGGUGCAGCUAGGGCAUUAAUCCGGGUCUGUAUGUCCCUAGAACAUGUGCUCUUAACCACCCCACCAGUAAAACUCAGGUCUUGGUGCAGACUCCAGAUCCUCUCUCAGGGACUGGAAAAUGGGCAUGUGGUGGAGGGGUGAUCACCAUAAACUCUUCAGCUCUGACUUGGGUGGCUGUGAGGACUCCUCCAGGUAGCUGCUGUGACCUUACCCCAUCUGGGCCAGAUUCUGGACAGAGGGCAGGGCCUAAUGCUAAGGGGGGUGAGCCGAAAGGUGGUCACCUGGGAUAUCUGAGCCACUUUCUGCAUUGUGCAGUGGGAAGGCUGAGGCCCAGAGAGGAGCAGUCACCACCCAAGGUCACACACCCUGUGAGCUGCAGGGCCCCGUGGGAUCCCAGGUCUCCUGGCCUCUUGAAAGGGCAGGGCUGGGUGUGGUGCCAGAGCGGGGAGGCUACCUCCUCCUGGGCCCCACCCACCAGCCUAGUUUCCUCCCUGGAUGUUGUGAGCACCCAGCUUCUAGGAGGGUGCAGGGGUCUGUUGGCAGACUCCUUAGGGCCAUGCUCCCUCCCCAUCAAUCUGAGCCCCUAGUGUCAGUUGUGCCGCUCCCUUUGGAACCCAUUGGGGUGGAAACUCCCUGGCAACAGCUGAUGGAUGGGUUAGGGCUUUGACAUUGGCCUGGGGCCACAGCAUGGCCCUGGAGGGACCAGGCUGGGGCUGGGAGGUGGGGGUUGGAGGGGAAUUUAAGGGAAAAGAAUUAGGCUCAUAAAUCAUGGAGCAUCUCGUUUCUCCUCCUCAACCUUAGUCUCUUAGCAAACCUGCUCUCCAACUGCUCAUCCAAGGUGCUGGGGGUUGAGGGAGCCCACCUGCCUGUUCCCCACUCCCUCCAGCUGAUGCUCAUCCCCUCCGGAAAUUGCACCCUCCCACGAGAAAGAAAGAGCUGCAGCCACUAUUGCUAGGCAGCAUUAAGACAAGUCCAGAUGACUGGAUUUUGCCUCUGACUCAUUGUGAUGAGUAGGGCGGAGGGCUUCACUGCCUCAGUUUCCCCAACUUUGGACCUUAAAUCCUCUCCUGAUGCCUCUCAGCCCAGCCAGGAAGGAGAGCUAAGACCAAGAGGGAUUUAACAGAUGCAGGACACACAGCCUUGUCCUCAGACCCCCCAAGUCUGAGAGAAGCAAAACACUCACCUUGAGAGCCCUCGGACUUGGAGAUGGGAGCUUGCCUGAUUGUCAACCCAUCGGCCUGGACCCCAGAGCCCACCCAGUUGAGCGUGUGCAGAGGGCCCCGAGUGCGGGGCGACGCUCAGGCCGUUGCAGAGACCACCCUGGAGAUGCUGAUGAAGACAGGCCUUUCCUGCUGAGCCCAGCCUAUCUUCGCAGCCUGCUCAGAAAGGGGAACUGAGGCUCAUGGAUAUACAGUGAGUCCUACCUCCUAGCCUGAGGACUCUUCCCUGCGCCUUGAUGACCUGAGAGAACUGGGAGGAGAAAGGGGUUGUGACAAUGACCAGGACUCAGGGCAGAGGUGGAAACCAGAGUGCCUGAUGUGUGCAGCUGCUGACCCCCCCAGGACACCUCUCUACCGGAGUCUGUGGAAGCAGAGAACUGGGAGGCCAAGGCGCUGUCCACGCCCCGAGGCCUGGGCUCAGGCCGAAGUUGCUCCACAGCACCCCCAGCUGACAGCCAGCGACUGGCAGAGCCCCCAGGCACGGGGGCCCUCUCUCUUCCAGAGAUCUCCAGUGUGACAGCCCAGGCGGCAGAGCCGAGGGUCCUGGUCCCGGCUUCUCGCACCCUCAUGUCAGCCCCGGCCCCGCCCGGCGGCCUGCGGAGGACAAGGUCAGGAUGCGUGUGAAGCCCCAGGGCCUGGUGGUGACUUCCAGUGCCGUGUGCAGCUCUCCUGACUACCUCCGGGAACCCAAGUACUACCCCGGCGGCCCCCCCACCCCCCGGCCCCUGCUUCCCACCCGGCCCCCUGCCAGCCCACCUGACAAGGCCUUCUCCACCCACGCCUUCUCCGAGAACCCACGCCCACCCCCACGCCGGGACCCCAGCACCCGGCGCCCACCAGUCCUUGCCAAGGGGGACGACCCGCUGCCCCCACGGGCAGCCCGUCCUGUCUCACAGGCCCGCUGCCCCACACCGGUCGGAGACGGCAGCAGCUCCCGACGCUGCUGGGACAACGGGCGGGUGAACCUGCGACCAGUGGUGCAGCUGAUUGACAUCAUGAAGGACCUGACACGCCUCUCCCAGGACCUGCAGCACAGUGGUGUACACCUGGACUGUGGUGGGCUCCGACUGAGCCGCCCGCCUGCACCGCCACCCGGCGACCUACAGUACAGCUUCUUCUCCUCACCCAGUUUGGCCAACAGCAUCCGUAGCCCUGAGGAGCGGGCCACCCCACACGCCAAGUCGGAGCGGCCCAGCCAUCCCCUCUACGAGCCUGAGCCUGAGCCUAGGGACAGUCCCCAGCCUGGCCAAGGCCAUAGUCCCGGAGCCACGGCUGCGGCCACGGGUCUGCCCCCAGAGCCUGAGCCAGACAGCACUGAUUACUCAGAACUUGCUGACGCCGACAUCCUUAGUGAGCUGGCCUCCCUCACUUGCCCAGAGGCCCAGCUGCUAGAGGCCCAGGCCCUCGAGCCACCAUCGCCCGAGCCGGAGCCUCAGCUCCUGGACCCCCAGCCCCGCUUCCUGGACCCGCAGGCACUAGAGCCGCUCGGGGAAGCUCUGGAGCUGCCACCCCUGCAACCUCUUGCUGAUCCUCUGGGGCUGCCGGGCCUGGCUCUCCAGGCCCUGGACACCCUGCCUGACUCCUUGGAGUCGCAGCUGCUUGACCCCCAGGCACUCGACCCCCUGCCCAAGCUGCUUGACGUCCCAGGUCGCCGUCUGGAGCCCCAGCAGCCCCUGGGGCACUGCCCACUGGCCGAGCCCUUGCGCCUGGACUUGUGCUCACCGCACGGCCCCCCCGGGCCUGAGGGUCACCCCAAGUACGCCUUGCGGCGCACUGAUAGGCCAAAGAUCCUGUGUCGCCGGCGGAAAGCCGGACGGGGACGCAAGGCAGACGCCGGACCCGAGGGCCGCCUACUGCCCCUGCCUAUGCCCACGGGGCUGGUGGCUGCCCUGGCCGAACCCCCACCACCACCGCCUCCUCCACCCCCUGCCCUGCCAGGCCCAGGCCCGGUCUCAGUCCCAGAGUUGAAGCCGGAAUCUUCCCAGACCCCAGUGGUCUCUACCCGCAAAGGCAAGUGCCGGGGCGUGCGGCGCAUGGUGGUGAAGAUGGCCAAGAUCCCCGUAUCGCUGGGGCGGCGGAACAAGACCACAUACAAAGUGUCUUCCUUGAGCAGCAGCCUGAGCGUGGAGGGCAAGGAGCUGGGCCUGCGCGUGUCGGCUGAGCCCACCCCGCUGCUGAAGAUGAAGAACAAUGGGCGGAACGUGGUAGUGGUCUUCCCACCCGGUGAGAUGCCCAUUAUUCUCAAACGUAAGCGCGGCCGCCCUCCUAAGAACCUGCUGCUGGGUCCCGGCAAGCCCAAGGAGCCAGCUGUGGUGGCGGCCGAGGCAGCCACUGUGGCAGCGGCCACCAUGGCCAUGCCAGAGGUAAAAAAACGACGGCGGCGGAAGCAGAAGCUGGCAUCUCCCCAGCCAUCCUAUGCAGCAGACGCCAACGACAGCAAGGCCGAGUACUCAGACGUCCUGGCCAAGCUGGCCUUCCUGAACCGCCAGAGCCAGUGCGCUGGACGGUGCUCACCGCCCCGCUGCUGGACACCCAGUGAGCCGGAGUCGGUGCACCAGGCCCCCGACACCCAGAGCAUCUCCCACUUCCUGCAUCGUGUGCAGGGCUUCCGGCGGCGUGGGGGCAAAGCAGGCGGUUUUGGUGGCCGGGGUGGGGGCCAUGCGGCCAAGUCAGCCCGAUGCUCCUUCAGUGACUUCUUUGAGGGCAUCGGCAAGAAAAAGAAGGUGGUGGCCGUGGCAGCCGCUGGGGUCGGGGGCCCGGGCCUUACUGAGUUGGGGCACCCACGCAAACGGGGCCGGGGGGAGGUAGACGCUGUGACUGGGAAGCCAAAGCGCAAGAGACGGUCCCGGAAGAAUGGGACUCUGUUCCCAGAGCAGGUGCCCAGUGGCCCAGGCUUUGGGGAGGCAGGUGCUGAGUGGGCCGGGGAUAAGGGUGGUGGCUGGGCCCCUCACCAUGGGCACCCAGGCGGACAAGCUGGCCGAAACUGUGGGUUUCAGGGGACCGAGGCCCGGGCCUUUGCCUCCACUGGGCUGGAGAGUGGAGCCUCAGGCCGUGGCAGCUACUACAGCACGGGUGCACCCUCAGGCCAGACCGAGCUCAGCCAGGAGCGCCAAAACCUCUUCACCGGCUACUUUCGCUCGCUGCUCGAUUCGGAUGACUCCUCCGAUCUCUUGGACUUUGCCCUCUCAGCCUCUCGCCCAGAGUCCCGGAAGGCAUCGGGCACCUAUGCAGGGCCACCCACCAGUGCCCUGCCUGCCCAGCGGGGCCUGGCCACCUUCCCUAGCCGGGGAGCCAAGGCCAGCCCAGUGGCAGUGGGUAGCAGCGGGGCUGGGGCGGACCCCUCCUUUCAGCCUGUCCUGUCCGCGCGCCAGACCUUCCCACCAGGACGAGCAGCAAGCUAUGGGCUAACUCCAGCCGCUUCAGACUGCCGGGCAGCCGAGACCUUCCCCAAGCUGGUGCCCCCGCCCUCAGCCAUGGCCCGCUCACCUACCACCCACCCGCCUGCCAACACCUACCUGCCCCAGUACGGCGGCUAUGGGGCCGGACAAAGCGUAUUCGCCCCAACUAAGCCCUUUACAGGCCAGGACUGCGCUAACAGCAAGGACUGCAGCUUCGCCUAUGGCAGUGGCAACAGCCUCCCUGCCUCACCCAGCAGCGCCCACAGCGCCGGCUAUGCCCCACCGCCUACCGGGGGCCCCUGCCUGCCACCAAGCAAGGCCUCCUUCUUCAGCAGCUCUGAGGGGGCCCCCUUCUCUGGUUCAGCCCCCACGCCCCUGCGCUGUGACAGCCGGGCCAGCACAGUCUCGCCCGGUGGCUACAUGGUACCCAAGGGCACCACAGCCUCUGCCACCUCUGCAGCCUCUGCCGCCUCCUCCUCCUCCUCCUCCUUCCAGCCCUCGCCCGAGAACUGUCGGCAGUUUGCGGGGGCUUCUCAGUGGCCUUUCCGGCAGGGCUAUGGAGGCCUGGACUGGGCCUCAGAGGCCUUUAGUCAGCUCUACAAUCCCAGUUUUGACUGCCACGUCAGCGAGCCCAACGUGAUCCUGGACAUCUCCAACUACACACCGCAGAAGGUGAAGCAGCAGACGGCUGUGUCGGAGACCUUCUCUGAGUCAUCCUCCGACAGCACCCAGUUCAAUCAGCCGGUUGGUGGCGGGGGGUUUCGGCGUGCCAACAGCGAGGCCUCAAGUAGUGAGGGCCAGUCGAGCCUGUCCAGCCUGGAGAAACUGAUGAUGGACUGGAACGAGGCAUCAUCUGCCCCCGGCUACAACUGGAACCAGAGUGUCCUCUUUCAGAGUAGCUCCAAGCCGGGCCGUGGACGGCGGAAGAAGGUGGACCUGUUCGAGGCCUCACAUCUGGGCUUCCCGACAUCCGCCUCUGCCGCUGCCUCAGGCUACCCAUCCAAACGGAGCACUGGGCCCCGGCAGCCGCGAGGUGGACGGGGCGGUGGGGCCUGCUCAGCCAAGAAGGAGCGGGGUGGCGCAGCGGCCAAAGCCAAGUUCAUCCCCAAGCCACAGCCAGUCAACCCACUGUUCCAGGACAGUCCUGACCUCGGCCUGGACUACUAUAGCGGGGACAGCAGCAUGUCACCACUGCCCUCACAGUCGAGGGCCUUCGGCGUGGGAGAGCGAGACCCCUGUGACUUCAUAGGACCCUACUCCAUGAACCCGUCCACGCCUUCCGAUGGCACCUUUGGCCAAGGCUUCCACUGCGACUCGCCCAGCCUGGGUGCUCCCGAGCUUGAUGGCAAGCAUUUCCCACCGCUGGCCCACCCACCCACGGUGUUUGACGCCGGCCUGCAGAAGGCAUACUCGCCCACCUGCUCGCCUACACUGGGCUUCAAGGAAGAGCUGCGGCCACCGCCCACAAAGCUGGCUGCCUGCGAGCCCCUCAAGCAUGGACUCCAGGGGGCCAGCCUGGGCCACGCAGCUGCAGCCCAGGCCCACCUGAGCUGCCGGGACCUGCCGCUGGGCCAGCCCCACUACGAUUCCCCCAGCUGCAAGGGCACAGCCUAUUGGUACCCUCCAGGCUCAGCUGCCCGCAGCCCGCCCUAUGAAGGCAAGGUGGGUACAGGGCUGCUGGCUGACUUCCUGGGCAGGACGGAGGCCGCGUGCCUCAGUGCCCCUCACCUGGCUAGCCCACCAGCCACGCCCAAGGCCGACAAGGAGCCACUGGAAAUGGCCCGGCCCCCUGGCCCACCCCGUGGCCCUGCUGCAGCCGCUGCUGGCUAUGGCUGCCCACUCCUUAGUGACUUGACCCUGUCCCCCGUGCCGAGGGACUCGCUGCUGCCCCUGCAGGACACCGCCUACAGGUACCCAGGCUUUAUGCCCCAGGCGCAUCCUGGCCUGGGUGGGGGCCCCAAGAGCGGCUUCCUGGGGCCCAUGGCGGAACCUCACCCCGAGGACACAUUCACCGUCACAUCCCUGUAGUGCCAACUGAAGUGCCGACUGGACCGCGAGGUUUUGUUCCUGGCUUUCAGAAAACCAACGCCAAGAUCCCUCCCAGCGUCCACAUCGUCCUCUGGCAGGAGCUCCUGCCCCUCUGCCUCCCACCCUGCCCCCUACACCCCCUGCAGACCCAUCUCCCUCCACCCCCUCCCACCCAUCUCCUCCACGCAGAAGCCGAAGGUGAGCCCUUUCUGCACAAAACCAGCAAUUGUAAAUACUUUUUAAAAAUGUACAAAACUUAAAAACAAAACACAGUUUUAGAAAAAGACAAAAAAAAAAAAGAGAGAGAGAGAGCGAGAGAGCGAGCGUGUGCAAGAGGUUGCGAGCGGGGCCCCGAGGUGUCCAGAGCCCCUGCAAGUAUGCACUGAGAAAUUUAUCUACAGGUCGUUUGACAAAAAUGAACAAUAUCCUAUUUAUUGUAUAUACUGUUUUAUUAUAAAUCGUGGAUUGUAUAUUGCAUUCUGUAAACCUGCUGUGGUCCCGUGGUGUGCAAAUUCGCAUGGUGGGGGGGAGGGAGAAGAACCUCUUGCGGGAGCUUUUUUUUUCUUUCUUAUUUUUCACUCUUUUGGGUUUUCUCUUCUGUUGUUGUUGUUGUUGUUUUCUGUUGGCAGGACACACCCAAAGAUCCAAGUUUGUAUUAAAAAGAAAUGAAAAAAAGCAAAAAAAAAACAAAAAAAAAACAAAAAAAAAAAACCAA